GAUAGAUGUCCAUUAAAAUUAUUAAUAUCUGAGUAUCAAUCUUUAUAGUGAGGAUGAAGUUGAGGAAAUGUGGAAAUUCUCUACAGAAACACAAUACGUACACAUUGCCUCUCCCCACAAAAAUCAUUGGUAAUAAAUGUGCCUAUUGGAUAAUAAAAUGUGGUCAUAAAAUGAGUAGAAUUGUCACUAAUUAUGUUAGCAUGCAUCUCUUCCGUGCACACAGAAAGAAAUGAAUAAUAGAUCCAAAAAAGAUUUGAUAAGGAUCACAAAAGAGAAAUGAAGAACAAAUCAAUGGAAAUAGAGUUCAUUCUCCUAGGAUUGACAGAUGACCCACAGUUGCAAAUUGUGAUUUUCCUGUUUCUAUUUCUCAACUACACCUUGAGCCUGAUGGGGAACUUAAUCAUCAUCAUCCUCACCCUGCUGGAUCCCCGGCUCAAGACGCCAAUGUAUUUCUUUCUCCGUAAUUUCUCCUUUUUGGAAGUAAUAUUCACAACAGUGUGUAUUCCUAGAUUCUUGAUAACCAUUGUGACUAGAGACAAAACCAUUUCUUAUAAUAAUUGUGCAACUCAAUUAUUUUUUAUCCUUUUACCGGGAGUUACUGAGUUUUACCUCCUGGCUGCCAUGUCCUAUGACCGCUACGUUGCCAUCUGCAAACCACUGCAUUAUCCAAUCAUUAUGAGCAGCAAAGUCUGCUACCAACUUGUACUUAGCUCUUGGGUAACUGGAUUCUUAAUCAUAUUUCCCCCAUUGGUCAUGGGACUCAAGCUGGAUUUUUGUGCUUCCAAAACUAUUGACCACUUUAUGUGUGAAACUUCUCCUAUUCUGCAGAUCUCCUGCACAGAUACCCAUGUCCUAGAAUUGAUGUCUUUUACCUUAGCUGUGGUGACACUUGUGGUCACACUGGUAUUAGUGAUUCUCUCUUACACUUGCAUUAUUAAGACCAUUCUGAAAUUCUCUUCUGCACAGCAAAGGAACAAAGCAUUUUCCACCUGUACUUCCCACAUGAUUGUUGUCUCCAUGACAUACGGUAGCUGUAUCUUUAUGUAUAUUAAACCAUCUGCAAAAGAAAGAGUGACUGUAUCCAAAGGUGUAGCUUUGCUCUAUACCUCAAUUGCCCCUUUACUAAAUCCCUUCAUUUAUACUCUCAGAAACCAGCAGGUGAAAGAAGUCUUCUGGGAUGUAUUACAAAAGAAUUUGUGUUUUUCUAAAAGACCAUUUUAAGAAUCUGCUACAAAUUACAACUUUACCAUAAAAACUGGAAAACGGCCUGGCAUGGUGGCUCAUGCCUGUAAUCACAGCACUUUGGGAGGCUGAGGAGGGUGGUUACCUGAGGUCAGGAGUUCGAGACCAGCCUGGCCAACAUGGUGAAACCCCGUCUCUACUUAAAAGUACAAAAAUUAGCUGGGCGUGGUGGAGAGUGCCUGUAAUCCCAGCUACUCAGGAGUCUGAGGCAAGAGAAUAGCUUGAACUCGGGAGGUGGAGGUUGCAGUGAGCCCAGAUGGUGCCACUGCACACCAGCUU